AGUCAAGAAAUUGGAGCAUGGCUAUGAGCAAUGGAAACAAUGAUUUUGUGGUUCUGAGCAACAGCAGCAUCGCAACCAGUGCUGCUAACCCGAGUCCCCUCACCCCCUGUGAUGGAGACCAUGCAGCCCAGCAGCUCACACCCAAAGAAGCAACAAGAACAAAAGUGAGUCCAAAUGGAUGCCUGCAACUUAAUGGCACGGUCAAAUCAUCCUUUCUGCCUUUAGACAACCAAAGAAUGCCUCAGAUGUUACCCCAAUGCUGCCAUCCUUGCCCAUACCAUCACCCUUUGACUAGCCAUAGCAGUCACCAAGAGUGCCAUCCCGAGGCUGGCCCUGCAGCACCCUCUGCUUUGGCCUCGUGUUGCAUGCAGCCACACUCCGAGUAUUCUGCAUCUCUUUGUCCAAAUCAUUCACCUGUGUAUCAGACUACGUGCUGUCUUCAGCCCUCUCCAUCCUUCUGCCUGCAUCAUCCGUGGCCUGACCAUUUUCAGCAUCAGCCUGUGCAACAGCACAUAGCCAACAUAAGAUUCACCAGAAAAACUAAGUGUGCUUCAUGGCUUCUUCAGAUGUGAACGUGUUCACUGAAAGCCCAGUCUGUGUAAAGCUGCUAAGCCCUCACCAGCUCACUGGAGUGGCCCUGCACUCCGUCCCUCUAUGCAUACUUGGAUAGCCCUGGCCAGCUGAGCGCUGCAGGUCAGGAGGCUGCUGUCUCCUACAGCCACACACUUCUGCUCCCAGCAUUUGACAAGUGUGCUUACCAAACCCACGCAUGCCAGUUGGCUUGUUUUGACCAUCCAGACCUUUCAAGUUGCCAAAAAGAUUCAAGAAGCCAGAAGUUUGCAGGAUGCAUUUUGAAUUUUAGAAAACGUUCAGUUUAGUCAGCUUCUGUUGGGUACUCAGCUCAUAUCAAGACUUGGAAGUGCCAAAAUAAUAACGUGUGAUCCAGGACCUCAUGGAAGGGAUACAGAAACAGAUCUUUCAAUUUGAGUUAUGCAGCCCUGAUAGCCGACUGGCCGGUGGUGGUCUUGGGCAUGUGCACCAUGUUCAUCGUAGUCUGUGCCUUGGUUGGAGUAUUAGUGCCAGAGCUCCCUGACUUCUCUGAUCCAUUGCUGGGUUUUGAACCAAGAGGAACAGCAAUAGGCCAGAGAUUGGUCACAUGGAAUAAUAUGGUGAAAAAUACAGGAUACAAAGCAACAUUAGCAAAUUAUCCCUUUAAAUAUGCAGAUGAACAAGCCAAAAGCCAUCGGGAUGAUAGAUGGUCAGAUGAUCAUUAUGAAAGAGAGAAAAGAGAAGUUGACUGGAACUUCCACAAGGACAGCUUUUUCUGCGACGUUCCAAGUGACCGAUAUUCCAGAGUGGUAUUUACUUCAUCUGGAGGGGAGACAUUAUGGAAUUUACCUGCAAUUAAAUCAAUGUGCAAUGUAGAUAAUUCCAGGAUCAGAUCUCAUCCCCAGUUUGGUGAUCUCUGCCAGAGGACCACUGCUGCCUCCUGCUGCCCCAGCUGGACACUGGGAAACUACAUCGCCAUUCUGAACAAUAGAUCGUCCUGUCAGAAAAUAGUUGAGCGAGACGUUUCUCAUACCUUGAAGCUGCUUCGGACUUGUGCCAAACACUACCAAAAUGGCACUCUGGGGCCAGACUGCUGGGACAUGGCAGCCAGAAGAAAGGACCAGCUCAAGUGCACCAAUGUGCCACGCAAAUGUACCAAGUACAAUGCUGUGUACCAGAUCCUCCAUUACUUGGUGGACAAAGACUUUAUGACCCCAAAGACGGCUGACUAUGCCACGCCAGCUUUAAAAUACAGCAUGCUCUUCUCUCCCACAGAGAAAGGGGAGAGCAUGAUGAACAUUUACUUGGACAACUUUGAAAACUGGAACUCUUCUGACGGCGUGACUACCAUCACCGGGAUUGAGUUUGGUAUCAAACACAGUUUGUUUCAGGAUUAUCUUCUAAUGGAUACUGUGUAUCCUGCCAUAGCCAUUGUGAUUGUCCUUUUAGUUAUGUGUGUCUACACCAAGUCCAUGUUUAUCACUCUGAUGACAAUGUUUGCAAUAAUCAGUUCUUUGAUUGUUUCCUAUUUUCUCUAUCGUGUAGUAUUUCACUUCGAAUUUUUUCCUUUUAUGAACCUCACUGCCCUCAUUAUUUUGGUUGGAAUUGGAGCAGAUGAUGCUUUUGUCCUGUGUGAUGUUUGGAACUACACAAAAUUUGAUAAGCCUCAUGCCGAAACCUCAGAAACAGUAAGCAUCACCUUGCAGCACGCUGCCCUCUCCAUGUUCGUCACCAGUUUUACCACUGCUGCUGCCUUUUAUGCUAACUAUGUUAGCAACAUUACAGCAAUCCGAUGCUUUGGGGUUUAUGCGGGGACAGCUAUAUUGGUGAAUUACGUUUUGAUGGUCACAUGGCUUCCAGCAGUUGUUGUGCUGCAUGAGCGGUAUCUUCUUAAUAUAUUCACUUGCUUCAAAAAGCCCCAGCAGCAAAUAUAUGAUAACAAAAGCUGCUGGACAGUGGCUUGCCAGAAGUGCCACAAAGUACUCUUUGCCAUUUCAGAAGCAUCUCGAAUUUUUUUCGAAAAAGUAUUGCCAUGCAUUGUCAUUAAGUUUCGCUACCUUUGGCUGUUUUGGUUCCUUGCCUUAACUGUAGGUGGGGCCUACAUUGUAUGUAUAAAUCCAAAGAUGAAACUGCCCUCACUGGAGUUAUCCGAGUUCCAGGUGUUCCGGUCGUCCCAUCCUUUUGAGCGUUAUGAUGCUGAAUACAAAAAGCUUUUCAUGUUUGAACGUGUUCACCAUGGCGAGGAGCUCCACAUGCCCAUCACAGUAAUCUGGGGCGUGUCCCCAGAAGACAAUGGCAACCCACUAAAUCCCAAGAGUAAAGGGAAGUUGACAUUAGAUAGCAGUUUUAACAUCGCCAGCCCAGCUUCCCAGGCCUGGAUUUUGCACUUCUGUCAAAAACUGAGAAACCAAACAUUCUUUUACCAGACUGAUGAACAGGACUUCACCAGCUGCUUCAUUGAGACAUUCAAACAGUGGAUGGAAAACCAGGACUGUGAUGAGCCUGCCCUGUACCCAUGCUGCAGCCACUGGAGCUUCCCCUACAAGCAAGAGAUUUUUGAACUGUGCAUCAAGAGAGCUAUCAUGGAGCUGGAAAGGAGUACAGGGUACCAUUUGGAUAGCAAAACCCCAGGGCCGAGGUUUGAUAUCAAUGAUACUAUCAGGGCAGUGGUGUUAGAGUUCCAGAGUACCUACCUCUUCACACUGGCUUAUGAAAAGAUGCAUCAGUUUUAUAAAGAGGUGGACUCGUGGAUAUCCAGUGAGCUGAGUUCGGCCCCUGAAGGCCUCAGCAAUGGUUGGUUUGUCAGCAAUCUGGAGUUCUAUGACCUCCAGGAUAGCCUCUCCGAUGGCACCCUCAUUGCCAUGGGGCUGUCAGUUGCUGUUGCAUUUAGCGUGAUGCUGCUGACAACUUGGAACAUCAUCAUAAGCCUUUAUGCCAUCAUUUCAAUUGCUGGAACGAUAUUUGUCACUGUUGGUUCUCUUGUCCUGCUGGGCUGGGAGCUCAAUGUGUUGGAAUCUGUCACCAUUUCGGUUGCCGUCGGCUUGUCUGUAGACUUUGCCGUCCAUUAUGGGGUUGCCUACCGCUUGGCUCCAGAUCCCGACCGAGAAGGCAAAGUGAUCUUCUCUCUGAGUCGCGUGGGCUCUGCGAUGGCCAUGGCUGCCCUGACCACCUUCGUGGCAGGGGCCAUGAUGAUGCCCUCCACAGUUCUAGCUUACACCCAGCUGGGCACCUUCAUGAUGCUCAUCAUGUGUAUCAGUUGGGCUUUCGCCACCUUCUUUUUCCAGUGCAUGUGCCGGUGCCUUGGACCACAGGGUACCUGUGGUCAGAUUCCUUUACCUAAAAAACUACAGUGCAGUGCCUUUUCCCAUGCCUUGUCUACAAGUCCCAGUGACAAGGGACAAAGCAAAACACAUACCAUAAAUGCUUAUCAUUUAGAUCCCAGGGGCCCAAAAUCUGAACUGGAGCAUGAGUUUUAUGAAUUAGAACCUCUGGCUUCCCACAGCUGCACUGCCCCUGAGAAGACCACUUAUGAAGAGACCCACAUCUGCUCUGAAUUUUUCAACAGCCAAGCAAAGAAUUUAGGGAUGCCUGUGCAUGCAGCUUACAACAGUGAACUCAGCAAAAGCACUGAAAGUGACGCUGGCUCUGCCUUGUUACAGCCCCCUCUUGAACAGCAUACCGUGUGUCACUUCUUCUCUCUGAAUCAGAGAUGUAGCUGCCCAGAUGCCUACAAACACUUGAACUAUGGCCCACACUCUUGCCAGCAGAUGGGGGACUGCUUGUGCCACCAGUGCUCUCCUACCACUAGCAGCUUUGUCCAGAUCCAAAACGGCGUGGCACCUCUGAAGGCCACACACCAAGCUGUCGAGGGCUUUGUGCACCCCAUCACGCACAUCCACCACUGUCCCUGCCUGCAGGGCAGAGUAAAGCCAGCCGGAAUGCAGAAUUCUCUGCCUAGGAAUUUUUUCCUCCACCCAGUGCAGCACAUUCAGGCCCAAGAAAAAAUUGGCAAGACCAAUGUACACAGUCUUCAGAGGAGCAUAGAAGAGCAUCUUCCAAAGAUGGCAGAGCCAUCGUCAUUUGUCUGCAGAAGCACUGGAUCGUUACUCAAAACGUGUUGCGACCCCGAGAAUAAACAAAGGGAACUCUGUAAAAAUAGAGACGUGAGCAAUCUGGAGAGCAGUGGAGGGACUGAAAACAAGGCAGGAGGGAAAGUGGAGCUGAGCUUGUCACAGACGGAUGCAAGUGUGAACUCAGAACAUUUCAAUCAGAAUGAACCAAAAGUCCUAUUUAAUCAUUUAAUGGGGGAGGCUGGUUGUAGGUCUUGCCCAAAUAAUUCACAAAGUUGUGGCAGAAUUGUGAGAGUGAAGUGCAAUUCUGUGGACUGUCAAAUGCCAAACAUGGAAGCCAAUGUGCCUGCUGUAUUAACACACUCGGAACUUUCUGGUGAAAGUUUGUUAAUAAAAACACUAUAAUAAAUGCAGCAUUCAAUUCAGAA